GAUUCUUGUGCCUUAGCCUCUCAAGCUACAGGCACACACCACCACGUCCAGCUAAUUUUUGUAUUUUUAUUAGAGACGAGUUUUUGCCAUGUUGCCCAGGCUGGUCUUGAACUCCUGGCCUUAAGUGAUCCUCCUGCCUCGGCCUCCUUAAGGGCUGGGAUUACAGGCAUGAGCCACCACAGCCGGCCUAGUGUGAAAGCAGUUUUUAAGGACAGUUGAACAGGAAAGCUCCUGGAUUCCUGCACAUAGAUCUUGUGCCCCUCCAAAGUGCCGUAAGUACCGAUUUCUGCUGUCUUGAUUUAACUCAGUGUCUGGAGCUUACGAUCCUUCCUCUCUGUUUCCUUCAGUGGCGUAGCUUGGGGGUGUCAAUUAAAGAGUUAUUGCAAGAUCUCAGCCUCUGAAAGUUUAGCUUAUUCAUCAGCAAAACUUUAAGCAAGUCUCACCUCUUCUAAAUUAGAAUUGUAACCUUGACUUUAGUCUCAGAGUUAACAUUGUGCAGAAAAAGAAAACACUGCGCAGUGUUGAAGCAGUUUGCAAACUGAAAUGAUACAAAUGAAAAAUGCUAUGAUGUUUCUCAGUAGUCUCUGUAUUUGCAAAUGAGUCAGUUAGGAUUAGUUUUACCCACAAAUAACAACAACAGUAAAAAAAAAAAAAAAAGAAAGAAAGAAAGAAAGUGACCCAGCACUAUAAUACAAGUUUAUUUCUCUCUCACAUCAAGGAAGUUCAGGGUAGCCAGUCUGGGCUGGUUUAGCAACUCCUUGAUCAUCAUGGGUUCUGUGCUACCUGGUAGUCCAGGAUGGUUGCACAAGCUCCAGCCAUUGCAUCUGUAUCCCAAUCAGCAAGAAAAAGGAAGAAAGGCAUACCCCCUUUUCAGGAGGCUUCCUGGAAAUCACAUACAACAUACCUGGUUACAUCUCAUCAGUGACCUUAGUCACACAGCCAUACUUAGCUGCAAGACAAGCGAAGACAUUCAGAUUCUACCUCUUCUUCUUGAAAUAGAAAGGUGAGUUGCCAAUCCACUGUCAGCGUGACGACAGUUCAAGAGGUUUUCCUAGACACAGAGUUGAGUUAAUCCCGUCAUCUGUGUCAUCGUCUCUAUUUUGACAGCAUCUGUCAGGUGGUCAACCAGAGUUUAGGCAAGAAGACCUAUGACUUCUCUACACAGACAUGAUUAGGAUUAUCUUCUAAAUCAACCAAACUGACCAGCCCACCCUUUCAUUCUUCUGUGCAUCACAGAUCAUUUUUGAAAAAGAGUUUAGGACACAUCCAAUAGUAAGAGUGUAGUUUUAUAAAUCAGGACUCAGUCUUACAGUGGAAGAUUAUAUGGUAGUUAGUGUCAUGGAGAAAAGCUUCAUAUUAGAUUAGUUGAAUCGAUUGGGAUACAGAACCGUCUUUAGAGCAUGGCAUCGUUACAUUGCAGAUAAAGCAUGUAGGUAGAGAAUGAUAUCUUUGUUGGGGAGAGCCCCAAACUGCUCUUCAGGAACCUUUCUCCGAGAUUUGCAAGCCAAUUAGGCAUAAUGAAACCUUGUUUUUAAUGCAUAUCUUUUGCCAGUAUAAUAAACAUAAUAAUUAAAUGUUUAUAUAUCUUUCGUAUUUUCCUGUAUAAUACAACUAAUCAUAUUUUUGUCAGGCUGAGGACAUCUCAAGAGGAGGGAAAGGUGGCAAAUUGAGGGUCUGUUCUUCUUUUAUACCAGAUGGCAAUUAUAACAAAUUACUUCUGGACUUAGGGAUGGGGGAGGGGUGGGGAGAUGGGAACAUGAGAAUUAUUCCUGAUUUUUGUUACUUUUUGUCCUGUAAAAUAUGCUUACCAGGCCGGGCACGGUGGCUCACGCCUGUAUCCCAGCACUUUGGGAGGCCGAGGCAGGCAGAUCGCCUGAGGUCGGGAGUUCGAGACCAGCCUGACCAACAUGGAGAAACACUGUCUCUACUAAAAAUACAAAAUUAGCCAGGCGUGGUGGCACAUGCCUGUAAUCCCAGCUACUAGGAAGGGUGAGGCAGGAGAAUCACUUGAACCUGGGAGGCGGAGGUGGCGGUGAGCUGAGAUCACGCCAUUGCAUUCCAGCCUGGGCAACAAGAGCGAAACUCCGUCUCAAAAAAAAAAAAAAAAAUGCUUACCGGGACAUCUCAAGGACAUCAUUCCUUUGUCAACGGUACAAAGAUAACCUGAGACAUAAAGUGAAAAUGAUUUAUGGUUUUUUGUUUUCUUCCUUACAUUAAAUUUUCCAAUAACAUAUCGCUAAUAACAUAUUUCUUUUGUUUUGAGACGGAGUUUUGCUCUUGUUGCCCAGGCUGGAGUGCAGUGGUGCAAUCUCGACUCACCGCAACCUCCGCCUCCCAGGUUCAAGUGAUUUCUCCUGCCUCAGCCUCCCAAGUAGCUGGGAUUACCUGCCACCACAUCAGGCUAAUUUUUUGUAUUUUUAGUAGAGACGGGGUUUCACCAUGUUGGCCAGGCUGGUUUUGAACUCCUGACUUUGUGAUCCACCUGCCUUGGCCUCCCAAAGUGCUGGGAUUACAGGCGUGAGCCACGGUGCCUGGCCAACAUAUUUCUAAUAAUAUAUUAAUUUGAUAAACAGAAGUUAUUUUGGAAAUAAGCCAAAACAACAAAAAAUGCUCAUCCCUGCUUUUCAAGGCUAUUAUCUGUAGUUUGAGGUUUUAUCAAAUGUAGAUAUGAACUGCGGGCCUCUUCAGGAUGUCCUCAUUGCUUCUGUUAAUGCUUUUACCAUCCAGUACCACUGAACAGGCAGCAGGGUGCCUUCUUGGGCACACCGGAAGGACCCAGGAAAAGGAAGAUAGUGUGGCCUGUUCUUGUCUCCAUGCCCCAAAAUGGACCACUACACCAGUGGGGUAGGAAAUAGCAGGUGUGUUAUGGGUUGAGUUUGGAGACCUUGACUUGAUCAACCAUCUGCUCACCCAGGUCAUCUUUCCUUUUUUUGCAGAGGUGAGGUCUCACUAUCUUGCCCAGGCUGGUCUCCUGGGCUCAAGUGAUCUUACCGCCUUUACCUCCCAAAGUGCUGGUAUUACAGGUGUGAGCCACCAUGCCUGGUUCUUGUCACCAUUCUUAACAUCAGCAGCAGCAGAAAAACCCCCUGUUUAGCCUUCAAUGUUAAUUUCCUCCUUGAUCUAUGUGUUCUACACAAACCACUCCCUUGUUGUCCCCCAUAUAUUACAUUUGUGGACUCUUCUCAAACUCUGCAGCUCAGCCCUGGUUCCUGCUGAGCCUACAGCCCCAGGCCUGAGCAGCCGGCUGGGCCAAGUUACCCUCAGUCUCAAGAUGACUUCCUCACAAGGCAAAACAUUUCUCCAGCUGGGUUGGAGACCUAAGCUGGGGAACUGGGCUCUCACAUUCCAAGAUAGAGGUUUGCCUAUGGACCCCUGAAAGUAGGCGUGUAGAAGCAGGUUCCUCUGAUGGCAGAGGCCCUCUGUUUAUCUCUGAAAGAUCCUGAAUGCUAUGCUUCUUUCAUCCCCUCUGCCUUGAAUUCGCCUGCUUUCUAGGUGCGGUGGAGAAAGCUGGGAAAAGAGCCACCUCUGCUCCCAGGGGCCACUGAGAGGGUAGAACACUGACCGAAUCCCAGACUCACUACCUCAGGGGCUGAGAUGGGUCCAAAGGGGCCCUUAACCUCUCACUUGAUCACCUGACUCUUACCGCUGUCAUUGAUCUGACAUGUUCUCCUGGGCGCUGUCCCAGCUCUGUCCCAGCUUCUCAGCACUGUGUCCUGGUCAGCCCUGAGGGCUCAUUUCCUUUAUCCAUACUGAGGACCAAGACCUGUCUUUCCUGUAGGGCAGUGAGGGCCACGGGCUAGUGCCUGAGCCGAUGAGUGCACUGCUGGUACUGUGCUGAGCCCUGGACAAGGGUGUAGGUUGCUCUAAAAAACAACUUCCCAAUAUUCUACAAAAUAACGUUCAAACUGAACAGAGCUUGACUGAAGAUUCUUCUUACUUCAUUUGUUUUCAUGCUACAUUUUUGCUGUCCGGCUCCAAGUCUGUGACAAUGGGUCACGGGAUCAGUGCGAGUAACAGUGAAGAUGUUUUUCUUCAUCUUUGGGCUAUGAUUGUGCUUUGUGAUCCUAAGUAUAAAUACAUUGAGGCUGGGCACGGUGUCUCACACCUGUAAUCCCAGCACUUUGGGAGGCCAAGGCAGGUGGAUGCCUCGAGCCCAGGAGUUCGAGACCAGCCUGGGCAACAUGUCAAAACCCCAUCUCUACAAAAAAAAUACAAAAAUUAGCCAGGUGUGGUGGUGUGCACCUGUGGUCCCAGCUGCUCAGGAGGCUGAGGUGGGAGGAUCACCUGAGCCCUGGAGAUCAAGGCUGAAGUGAGUUAUGAUCGUACCACUGCACUCCAGCCUGUCUCAAAAAACAAAACAAAAAAAAUACAUACACUGACUAAUAACACCAGCAAUAUUGUUUCAUGGGAGCUGCCUCUGCUGUUUGUACCAAAACUGAGCAGAUUCUUUAGGCCAGGCCCGAGUAAUCAUUAAAUCGAUCUGCUUGUGAGAAACCGGUAGGUCUAGGCAUGAGCACAAAGUGGCAGGUCCGUCUCUUCCCUUCUUAAAUAAGGAAUCACCAGAGGUAGACUCUGUGCCUGUGACUCUUGAAUGUUUAACUGAAAUCCAGAGCAGCAAUUGCAUUUUAUAUGACACCAUGUGUGUGCAAAAACUGAAUCAAAAUCUUGUGAAACAGUGCUACUUUCACUUACUAUAUAUGAUGUAGUCUAAUAAUUUUCUAUCCUAUUUUAUUUCCUUUUUUUAAAUGCUGGUUGAAAUUCUGUAAAUUUAUAUAAUGACAAACUACUGGGACUCUAUCUUGGUUCAAAAGUCCAUGAUCAGCCUGCUUGUAUUGAGUUACUACAUUGUACGAUCUUAUAAUUGUAAAGUUUAAGAUAUUUUCCUUCUGUCUGUCUUAAUUUAUUCUGUAAUCUAAGUUGUCCUGCCAGGAAUGCUGGCAUAUUUACUUUGUUUUUGAAUUCAAUAAUCAUAGUUUCUCUUGCUAAGUUACAUUAAUGGUACCAAAAAAAAGUUACUGCAUGGUUUUUGAAACUGUUCUUUCCUAGGAAGUUUUAAAGUAAAAUGUUUUUACCUUUUAUUGUUUACACAGGUUAAGCAUCCCUAAUUCAAAAAUCCAAAAUCCAAAGAAGUGCUCAAAAAUCCAAAGUUUUUUGAGUGACAACAUGAUGCCACCAGUGGAAAAUUCCACACCUGAUCUCGUGUGGCGGGUUGCAGUCAGCAUGCAGUUAAAUCUUUCAUAUAUGCACAAAAUUAUUAAAACUAUUGUCCAGGGCCAGGCACAGUGGCUCACACCUGUAAUCCCAGCAUUUUGGGAGGCCAGGGCAGGCAGAUCACUUGAGCUCAGGAGUUCGAGACCAGCCUAGGCAAGGUGAUGAAACCCUGUCUCCUCUAAAAAUACAAAAAAAAAAAAAAAACAUUAGCUGGGCACGGUGGCACACACCUGUAGUCCCAGCUAUUUGGGAGGCUGAGGUGGGAGAAUCACUUGAACUGGGUGGCAGAGGUUGCAGUGAGCCAAGAUCAUGUCACUGCACUCCAGCCUGGGCAAACAGAGGGAGACCCUGUCUUAAAAAAAUAUAUAUACAUAUAUAUAUAUAGUUUAGGCUAUGUCUAUAAGGAGUAUAUGAAAUAUAAAUGAAUUUCAUGUUUAGACAGGGGUCCCAACCCCAAGAUAUCUCGUUAUGUAUAUGCAAAUAUUACAAAAUCUGAAAAAAUUUAAAAGCCAAAAAUCACUUCAGUCUGGUGCCAACCAUUUUUGCAUAAUUGCAUUUUCCAUGUUGCAUUUUGCAACCAUUUUGCAUAAUUCUGUACUUCUUUCCCUUUUGGGUUUGUUUUCAUAACUGCUCAGUAAAAAGUGUUCUGUGUCAUCUUUCCAUUAUUUUGGGCUAAAUCAUGUUAAUGGCCAAGCCUGUCAGAAUUCAUUUGUUUUGAGUUAACUUCCUGGUGUCCAGUUCUCAGGAGUUGCAAGAAUAGAGCUCUUCCCUCAUGCAAUCAUCCAAAAUCCCAGGCCUCUAACCAGGAUUGGGGAACACCACUGUUGGCCAAGAGCAGAAGGCUUAAAGCUCUGGUCAUAGUCAUGGCACUGUACAAACUGUUCUUGUUCCCUACAAGAACAUGGGAACUAUUUGGAUAAUGGAUUUAUGAAUUUAAUUCUGAUGGAUUUUUAUAAAGGAGCUAAAAAUAAGCCUAUAUAAUUUAUUACAUGUAUAAUCAUAUAAUUUUAAAUGUGUAUAAUUUAUAAUAUUCAUCGAAACAUUUCUUUUUGGAAAUUAAAUUUCACUUUGGUCAAAAUCAUCUUACAAAACAAGAUGACUCAUGAUGGUUCUAAAUAAUGUAAACCGGUGUCUGUAACUAAUUAAUGCUCUGGAGGAAGGAAAUUCUGAGUUCUGACACAAAAGCACGUCUAAGUGGUAUUGGUAUUUUCAAAGCUUUUACUACAACCAAAAAUAUGUUCACGUGUACCUGUCUCCUCUUUACACUGCUUACUUUCUCUAUCGCUUUUCCCAAAUACGUCCCCAGUAACUUCCUCAUGUUCUGUGCACCACCUCCAAUCUUCCCCUAAUGUGUAUGAACUUGGUCAUCACCAAAGAGGUGGAAAGGAAGAAGGGCAUGUGCUAAUAUUAAUAUUGAGGUUUGGGCUGGGUGUGGUGGCUCAUGCCUGUAAUCCCAGAAUUUUGGGAAGCCGAGGCAGGUGGAUCACGAGGUCAAGACAUUGAGACCAUCCUGGCCACAUGGUGAAACCCCGUCUCUACUAAAAAUACAAAAAUUAGCUGAGUGUGAUGGUGCACAACUGUAGUCCCAGCUACUCGGGAGGCUGAGGCAGGAGAAUUGCUUGAACCAGGGAGGUGGAGGUUGCAGUGAGCCGAGAUCGUGCCACUGCACUCCAGCCUGGCAACAGGGAGAGACUCUGUCUCAAAAAAAAAAAAAAAAAGAAAAAAAUUGAGGUUUGUGCCAGUUUCUUUUUCCUUUAGGUCUCCUGAUAUGUGUCUAGUUAGUUCUAUAUACUUCCUGGAAAUUCGACUCCAAGAUAUUUAAUAAAACUAAACAGGGUUAUAUGUUGAAUAGACAAAUCCUAAAGAGCAGAAAGGAUUUAGUGGUUAGUGAAAUUUCAUUGACUUAAGAUGAGUUGGAUCCUCAAAAUUAAUAUAUUCUAAACAAAGUUCUAUUUUUAAGCUGCAGUAAUAAUGCCGAAUUUCUCUUAUAGUUAAUUGAAUGAUUUAUCCUGGUGUUGUCUCCUGGUAGUCACUGAAAAAGUCAUUACAAUCCUCACUUUCUCCCCUUUAAUUCAAGUUCAGAAUUCAUGUGUUGCUGUGACUUUUUUUGAGUUUAUCUGCAGACAGCUGCCAUUGAAUAAACAUGUUUAUAUAGGGCAGAAAAAGGCAGCCUGAAGAUUCUACUUUCUAUUUCUUUUAGCACUGUUUGGCAGUUAACACCAACAGCGCUUCAGAAUGAGGUACUGUCCAGCAUACACCUUGCUUGUUCCUCUACAAAGCUUCUAUUUUUGUUUUUGAUUUGUUGUGAGGAAGCAAAGUGUAGCCUUUACUUGAAUGAAAGCUACAGUUUUAUUUUUCUUUCUUAUUUACAAGAAAUUCUUUUGAUGAUUAAGUUAGCCAGAUACGCCCCGUGCGCUCAUAUUUCUUAACCUAUUUUGAGCUGAGCUAGUUGCAAGGACUAGUUCUUCUGUGAAACCUCUGGCAGUCCAUAAAUUCAAGUUCGUGUCCAGACGUAAUGGUGAACUCAAUAUGUUGUAUAUUUGAUAUAUGUUUGUUGCACACAUGGAGAGAAAAGUUGCUACCAUUGUGAAGUAGCCAUGAAAUCCGACAGUUCUAAUUUCUUUAUCUUCUGAGUACCCAUGGAAUAAAGGACCUCUUAGUGCCAUAGCAAGGCAGAAGUUUAAUUUGCAAUUCUGGUGGCAACAUCCAGGUAUUUCAAGUAGAAAUUAAGAAAACUUUACGGAAAAACUAUCUCAGCACUUCAGUUUAACUAUUUUUCAAAGUCCAAGGAGGGUUUUCCCCAGUGUAAAAGCAGAAAUGAGAAUUUCAGAUCUAAAGCGGUUCUUGCCUUUUCUUUUCCCUCCAUGCACAUGUGCUGACAACAGAAAGUAAAAUUUGAAAAGAAAACCCAGGCUAGAGCAUUGGGGUCACUCAUUUCCCAUCCAGCGAAGGGAGAGCUGGUGCCUGGCUGGGGGAGGUUAGGAAGGCAAGUCUUGGGAUCUGAUCACUCGGCUGGGAGUGGGUAAAAUACCUGGACCUCAGGAGGCCGGAUUGCAGCGCCAGUGUUCUCUACCUGUGUGGCCUGUUCCUGCCUGGGGUUGGGUACCAAGUCCAGGUGGAAGUGGUCCCUGGAGCAUCCUCUCUCUGAAGUGUUUCUUUGUCAAACAGAAUACUCCCUGCUGCUGCCCCAGAACUCAUCACUGUUGACACAUGGACCAAGAACUAGCAGAGGAGGUGAUUUAUAAUCUCUAAAUGAAUUGCUCUAAAAGAGACAACAAGCACUCUGACUUAAGUAAAGGAAGGGAGGGUGGGUGGAAAGGAAGGAGGAUCAUAAAGAACAUUCUAGAUUGCAUACUUUGGUAAUCACAGCAGGGCCUUAUUGCAGUUAGAACAAAAGCCUGGACACACUUACCUCUCAGUUCAGGAAAAUAAUUUAGAGCUACUUGUUAAAUGCUGGAGUAUUAUUGAAGUACCAAGUGUUAAGAUUUUCACUGAAAGCAAAACUGACCAAGCAGCUCAGCUAGGGAAAUGCUAUGUGAUCAGUUGAUUGUUUGAUGAGGAGUAUGGAGCAGGGACUUUGGCAGAGGUUGCUAGCAGACAGGCCUUGGUUUUAGUCCAAGCUCUAUCGCUUAAUAGCUGUGUGACCUUGGGGAAAAUUAUAAAAUUUUCCAGUCCUUAGUAUCAUAAACUGUAAAUGGAGGAGAAAGAUGCCUCACAGAUGUUGAAGGUGAAGUGAGACAGGACACCUAGUACAUUGCCUGGCUACAUAGAAAAUGUUUCACAAAUGUUAACUUGAGGCCCUCUCCCCAUGCCUCGGUCUCUUAGAAUGGUUUUUCCCCAUCGUGUGCACAUUGAGCGGUAAGGCGGACAGCUGCCGCCGCCCAUGCUGCCCCAUGUUGAGAGCAUUUCUGUUGACCUUCCCUUCUUCCCUGUGAAGCUGGUUCAGCAGUCACCUCAUCACUGUUUUUCUUCUCCAGAGAGUGCUGGGUUGUAGCGACCAUACUGUUGACGCAACACAUCCCAACCACGCUGGACGGAAUUUUUACUGCGAUAAUUCAUAUUCCAGGAUCUUACAGUGCACAGGGUUACAACGAUUAGCAUAAUGAUCUUGCACAAUCUUUCUGCCUAGCAUGUAGUGCAUUCGUAAUAUUCUCAGAGGAGGCGUCUAGAAAGCGCCAGGCUCCUUCCUCCUGCGUGAGCCACUGCAAGCUGUCGGCGCCUCAGUGCUAUGGAGACCUUGGGUGGAUUAUUCCUUGUUGGCGGGGGGAGGGUCCCAGCUGUCCUGUGCAUUAUAGGAUAUUUAGCAGCAUCCUUGCUAGAUGCCAUUUACAACAAUCAAAAAUGUCUCCAGGCAUUGCUAAGUGUCCAGGUGGGGAGCGGAAUAGGCAGAACCGCCUCCAGUCGAGAAGGGCUGAACUGUACUUAGGAUUUGUGAUUCUGCAGAAAUGGGUUCUGUGAAUGCACUAAAGCAUGAGAACAUCCAAAAAUCAGUGUGGCACAGAACUGAAUUCAAAUUUACCUGGAUCCAGGUAAAUAAGCACAAUUUUGAAAGUACCAAACAGAAUUCAAGAAAAACAACAACAACAACAAAAAACACAUUAAAAACAGAAAAGUUGGCCGGGCGCCGUGGCUCACGCCUGUAAUCCCAACACUUUGGGAGGCCGAGGUGGGCGGAUCACCUGAGGUCAGAAGUUCGAGACCAGCCCGACCAACAUGGUGAAACCCUGACUCUACAAAAAAUACAAAAAUUAGCCGAGCGUGGUGGUGGGUGCCUGUAGUCCCACCUACUCGGGAGGCUGAGGCAGGAGAAUCGCUCGAACCUGGAGGGCGGAGGUUGCAGUAAGCCGAGAUCGCACCAUUGCAUUCCAGCCUGGGCAAAAAGAGUGAAACUCCAUAUCCAAAAAAAAAGGGGGGAAAGGUCAGAAAGACGUUCUUUUUCACUAGGUGAUGAAUUAAUCUUUCCCAUCUUUGUCAUGUUAAAAAUGUGCCUGUGGCUGUUUCUCCACUAAAUGAAGACACUGGCACACAGAUGAUUGUGUGUAAACACUAGGCAAGACACUAGGCACAAUCGUAGGGGUUCAGUAAUUAUUGAAUGAGAAGAAAGAAAGGUUGUUCUUGAAUUCUGUGAUGUGAGUGUUUAAUGAUGUUUUUGAGGAGAAUGCCAUAUGUAGCAGACAGAACCCUGGGCUGGGCAUCAGAGGGACCGGGGGCACCACACUGGGCUUUGUGUCAUUAUCUCCAGAAAGUAACUGGCCUGGUGCACAGGAGAAAGUUAGAGUACAUUGUCCAUACAGUUCCCACAUAGCUGUAGGGUUUUAUGAACCCAUAUUUUAAAGGGCCUUCUAAUGAAGUGAGGAUGUUAAUGCUUUUUUUUAAAAAAAAAAAAAAAAAAAGAGAGAGAGAGAUUGGUGAUUACUUUAAAAUCUGAGUCCUGGCCAGGACUCACGCCUGUAAUCCCAGCACUUUGGGAGGCUGAGACGGGCAGAUCAUUUGAGGUCAGGAGUUCGAGACCAGCCUGGCCAACAUGGUGAAAUCCUGUCUCUACUAAAUACAAAAAUCACGCUCCUGUAAUCCCAGUUACUUGGGAGGCUGAGGCAGAAGAAUCACUUGAACGUGGGAGGCGGAGGUUGCAGUGAGCCAAGAUCACACCACUGCACUCCAGCCUGGGCAACAGAAUGAGACUCCAUCUCAAAACAAACAAAAAAAUCCAAGUCCUAAUUAUCGCUGCAGCUUUCUUUAAUGUGUGCAGUAAGGUGGGGACAUACAGAAUAACUUAAGAUGUAGAAAUCGUCUCUCCCUCCCUGAAGAAUAUCAUGGAUACUACAUUUGCCUGCCAGGAAUGUUGUGUUGUUCUGGUGUUCUCGUUUCUGCCGUUAUCAUUGUUUCUGCUUAAUUUUUACAACACAACUCUGGCCGCACCCGUGGAUGAUCAUGGAAAGGCAGCUGCCUGGCUUUCCAGAAUUGUUUUGACUCUCCAUCUGAACCCAGAGCUCUGUUUCCUGUACAGGUUGCUAGCAGUAUUUACCCAAAUUGUCCCUUCCCAACUCAGACCCACUGACCCUUCCUUUCUCAGCUGAUUACGGGUUUAAGUUUGAAUCAAACCAUGCUAUAGAAUCACUAUCUAGCAGCUUCUGUGCUUGCACAAUAAGAGUAUUAGUCAGCGUUUCCUGUUUUCAUUCAUAUUGUAAGUUGAAUAGCUGUAACAAAAGGGAAAGAGAUUGCCAAGACAAAUAAUUCUUAUGGCUUGUGCAAACAAUUUAUUACAAGCCUUAUUAAAUAUGCAGCUUUCAGAAGUCUACGUGAUAUGCCUUUCAGCAAAGCUAAAUCCUACUAUGUGGACUUGCUUCAUGACUUAAGAACAAGUCUAUAUUGAAUUUAACAUUAAAUAAUUAUUUGGCCUGUAUCUCUUUUAAGCUUUGUUAAGAACUGCAAAUAUGAUAAGGGAAUAAAUUGCUCAUUUCAAGUCACUAAGAAAACCUAACCUAUAGGUUAUAUAUGUUGGCAGUUCCCAAGAAGUACCUAGGAAAUGGAACCUUCCUAUAAGAGUGGUUUGUCCCCUUCUCACGAGAUGGGUCUUCAUAUCAAGGCCCCCUAAGGCACAGAUACACAGCACUCCACAGUGUCCAAGUUCGUAGUAAUUGGUGGCACCUUAUUAAAGUAGUUUUUACUUUCAUAAUUACUGAUUACACAUCAGCAUACCUUUUCCAUGUUCUGUUUCCUUGGCAGCCUGAUAUUUGAAUACAAACGACAUAAAAGUGAUUACAUGCAGCAUUUCAGGACAGUUUUCAAACUGAGAGAAUUUGGCACUUUCUUUUAUUUUCUUCCCAUUCUUCGUCUAUUUCCUUUGCAUUUGGAAGCCAAACUCCUCGAACCUUUACUUCUGCAUGUUGUUUUCGUCCCCUAGCUAGAGUUCUCUUUAUUACUACUUUUUUGUUUCCAAUUGGUCUCUUUUUAAAAAUAAAACAUGGUGAAACCCCAUCAAUACAAAAAUUAGCCGGGCAUGAUGGCGGGUGCCUGUGAUCCCAGCUACUCGGGAGACUGAGGUGGGAGAAUCAAUUGAACCCAGGAGACGGAGGUUGCAGUGAGCUGUGAUCGUGCCAUUGCACUCCAGCCUGGGCGACAAGAGUGAAACUCCGUUUCAAAAAUAAAUGAAUAAGUAAAUUAAAAUAUGAAAUUAAGCUUAGCUAGCCUGUGUAGAUGUUUUAGAUGGUCAUAUCUUUAUCGGAUAUGACAUUUAUGCCUUUCAGUAAAACCAUUGUAGUAUUGUAAGAAAAAAAGGGAAGUAUGAUAGGGAGGACUAAGAACAUAUUUGUACUUCUAUGUAAUGCUAUUUUAUGUGUCUAUUUCCAUUGAAGUGUGGCCUUGACAUCACUGGCUCCCAAGUCCCAUCCUGUUUUUUCAUUGACCUGCUUGUGCCAGGUACUGCGUUAGGAAGUGGAGCUACCAGAUGAAUAAGGCGUGGUCCCGCCCUCCAUGUGGGAGACGGCACGUCAGUGUACUUAGGAUGCUGCAUGUGGUGACAGAUGAGGGCCCUGCAAGGGAGCACACCACAGGGCCGGGAGGGUGGGAUGGGCGGGAGGAGUAGCCAACUUUGCCCGAAAGCAUCAGGACAAGCUUCCAGGAAAUGGCACAUCCAAGCUGAGUCUUGGACAGCGGGUUAAAGAGGCAGAGAGGGGAGAGAGGAAUGUUCCACAUGGGAAAAGAGGUCUGGAGGUGACAACAAGUAACAUAGAGUAUGUGGGCUGUGCCGGAAGCUUGAUAUUACAGAGGCACGAAGUCUGAGGCAGGGAGUGUGAAGGAAGAUGAAGGUAGGGGAAGGAAGUUUACACAAGGGUGGCCUUGACUUUUAUAUUAAGGCACUUUAGGGAAGCAGGAACCACUGAAGACAGGAGAACAUGGUGACUACACGGGCGCAUUGAAGGGGGGAGGAGCUAGGUUUUUGAAGGGAAUUUGAGCUUGCAAUUUUUCAAGGGCAUUCAAUGGUUAUAAAUGAAACUUUUCAUUAAUAUAUUUGUGUCCAAGUGUUUUUAGAUGUGCUUUUCUGCUACUCUCUUUUUAUUUGGUUUGGAGAUAGAUGGUGACUUUCCUUCAGUGCCUUCUAUGUGUCUUGACAUGUUAAUGUCUCAAACACAUGGUCCGUAUCAUCAUGGAGCUUGCAAUCUAACAGGGUAGUUUAACACAUAAAUAUGCAUCCAGUUGGAAAGAACUUAGAGAUCACUUGAUCAGCCCCCGUUAUGUAAAAUGUAUGCAACAAUCUACCUCCAACUAUAGGGCGACAUUAAACAGUUUUUCAAAAUACCAUGGCAUUGAAAAAAAUGCGUAACAUUUGGGUUACUUCAGUCCCACUCCCCGGUACUAAUCAGGCCAGUGAACCAGUCUUGCUGGUGAAAUAAUGACUUCUCCAGUCAUGAUGGAUGAUUUCCCUUCAUCAUGACCAUUUCUUCCCUGGCUCUGCCUUUACCUAUGAAUCUCUUCUUUCCUCCCUCUCCUUCCUCCUCUUGGUCUCUGCCUGCCAUACCCAACUCCACAUUUCUCUGCUUGGAAAAAUCCUACUUGAUUCUCAGAGCCUGACUCCAUCACCCCCUCUCUCCAACCCUCCCAGGCAAACUCCGUCCCUCCCAGUGUGCCGCCCUCCAGCUCUCUCUAGUUGAAUAGCAGAUGUUCUCUCUCCCACUUCCCUGCAGGGCUUCAGGGUAGUGACCCUAAGAGUGAGCUUCUACCAGUGAGAAAAACGCCUGGAUGGAGCAGGAAUUCCCACAAAUGCUUAGGAAUUCAAUAUGAUUUUUAGCAAGUGGGAGAAUUAUCCUUUUGGUUACAAAGAUGUGAACUAUUUUUGUGAGUUCUCAGUAUGCACCAAGAAAAACCCCAGUGACUCAGUAAUGUACCUGUGCCGUCUCACUUAACCCUUCCAACAAGGAACUUGCCAAGGUGCACAGCUGGGAGGGAUCCGGGGUCCCGUCCGUGUGCUAACCUGCAGGACAGCGCCGCAUAAUCCAGUACUGGGGCCUUAUUGUCCAGCCUUCCACCUCCAGGAGCCCACUCAGUGAUGACUUUUGACAAAAGUCACCCGGAUUAUCCCUCUUUUGGGGUCCAUGAUGCCACCAACGGCUAAAGUUAACAAAUGCAUUACCAGGAGGUACCACUGAGGUAAGGAUUGUUACUGUAAGUGAUUUUCUCUGAUUUUGACCACUACAAGUAAAAUCACAAGAUUUGUCCCAAAUACUAUAUAAAGAGGAAUGUCUUUUAUUUCUCGAAAUUGUUCUGCCACUUUGUUUGUUCAAAUAACACAUAAUAAAGGAUAAAUGGCUUGUAGCUAUAUUUAUCCAAAUUGAACAUUUUUGAUGUAAUUUUUUUAAUUUGUCAAAAGCAUAUCAAUGGUCAUAAAAAUUUUUUAUGUCCUCUGGCCCUAUUACCUUACCCUUGGGAAUUUAUUCCAAGAACGUAAUUUGAAAGAGAUUAAAGCACAUAGGCACAAAUAUUUUCAGUGCAGUAUUGUUUAUAUUGGAAACAACCCAAAUGUUCAGUAACAGGGGGAACAAUUUUGUAAAUCUUGCUACAGCAACUUAACAAAAUUAUAAGCUGCCACUUAUAAUUGUAAAUUUUGAAAGUUUGUAGCACAGCAAGGAAACUGAUCAUGUUAAAUGUUUCUGAUAUCUUAGUUAAUUUUUCUCCCGCCAGUUCCGAUCGGUGUCCUGGUCAUACCGUCAGCAUAUAAUGACCGAAGCUGGCUUUGGUGCUGACAUCGGAAUGGAGAAAUUCUUCAACAUCAAGUGCCGAGCUUCCGGCUUGGUGCCCAACGUGGUUGUGUUAGUGGCAACGGUGCGAGCUCUGAAGAUGCAUGGAGGCGGGCCAAGUGUAACGGCUGGUGUUCCUCUUAAGAAAGAAUAUACAGAGGAGAACAUCCAGCUGGUGGCAGACGGCUGCUGUAACCUCCAGAAGCAAAUUCAGAUCACUCAGCUCUUUGGGGUUCCCGUUGUGGUGGCUCUGAAUGUCUUCAAGACCGACACCCGCGCUGAGAUUGACUUGGUGUGUGAGCUUGCAAAGCGGGCUGGUGCCUUUGAUGCAGUCCCCUGCUAUCACUGGUCCGUUGGUGGAAAAGGAUCGGUGGACUUGGCUCGGGCUGUGAGAGAGGCUGCGAGUAAAAGAAGCCGAUUCCAGUUCCUGUAUGAUGUUCAGGUUCCAAUUGUGGACAAGAUAAGGACCAUUGCUCAGGCUGUCUAUGGAGCCAAAGAUAUUGAACUCUCUCCUGAGGCACAAGCCAAAAUAGAUCGUUACACUCAACAGGGUUUUGGAAAUUUGCCCAUCUGCAUGGCAAAGACCCACCUUUCUCUAUCUCACCAACCUGACAAAAAAGGUGUGCCAAGGGACUUCAUCUUACCUAUCAGUGACGUCCGGGCCAGCAUAGGCGCUGGGUUCAUUUACCCUUUGGUCGGAACGAUGAGCACCAUGCCAGGACUGCCCACCCGGCCCUGCUUUUAUGACAUAGAUCUUGAUACCGAAACAGAACAAGUUAAAGGCUUGUUCUAAGUGGACAAGGCUCUCACAGGACCCGAUGCAGACUCCUGAAACAGACUACUCUUUGCCUUUUUGCUGCAGUUGGAGAAGAAACUGAAUUUGAAAAAUGUCUGUUAUGCAAUGCUGGAGACAUGGUGAAAUAGGCCAAAGAUUUCUUCUUCGUUCAAGAUGAAUUCUGUUCACAGUGGAGUAUGGUGUUCGGCAAAAGGACCUCCACCAAGACUGAAAGAAACUAAUUUAUUUCUGUUUCUGUGGAGUUUCCAUUAUUUCUACUGCUUACACUUUAGAAUGUUUAUUUUAUGGGGACUAAGGGAUUAGGAGUGUGAACUAAAAGGUAACAUUUUCCACUCUCAAGUUUUCUACUUUGUCUUUGAACUGAAAAUAAACAUGGAUCUAGAAAACCAA